AGUUGUCAACCGCGCCAGAUCCCCUUGAUGGCUGUGGCUUCGGAACCUCGCGGCCAGCACUGCCUUUUCGCCUUUUUAAAAUAUGGGAACACCCUGAUUUAAGCAGCGGUUGUCUUCCAGAAGGUCCUUUGAUUUUAGGGGGAAAUGCAUUAGCCAGGUCAAACAGCCGAUUUGAAACACAGAAGGCUAAGUUGACAUUUUACGUUAUUUUCUAAAGUUUAGGCCACUUGGUUCUUGGUUCUAAGCAGAGAUCCUUGGAACACACCUACCACCACCAUCAGAACCAUCACUACCCAUGCAUGGGGACCCAUUCUUGUGACAAGUUUGAGCGGCUUUAGAUCUUAUGAAGCCCACUGUCUCCCUUGGGCAGUGUGAGCAUGGGAGGAGCCAGACACAGGUGAUCAUAAGGUCCACAGAUUAUUAGAUGGCAUGUCAAAAAAUCCUUCAGGGAAAAACAGAGAAACUGUUCCAAUUAAAGAUAAUUUCGAAUUAGAGGUACUUCAGGCACAAUACAAAGAACUUAAAGAAAAGAUGAAAGUAAUGGAAGAAGAAGUUCUCAUUAAGAAUGGAGAAAUUAAAAUUUUGCGAGACUCACUACAUCAGACGGAAUCCGUUCUAGAGGAACAGAGAAGAUCACAUUUUCUUCUUGAGCAAGAGAAAACCCAAGCACUCAGUGACAAGGAAAAGGAAUUCUCCAAAAAGCUCCAAUCAUUGCAGUCUGAACUCCAGUUUAAAGAUGCAGAGAUGAAUGAAUUAAGGACAAAGCUCCAGACCAGUGAACGAGCAAAUAAACUGGCUGCUCCCUCUGUUUCCCAUGUCAGUCCUAGGAAAAACCCUUCUGUGGUUAUAAAGCCAGAAGCAUGUUCUCCACAAUUUGGAAAAACAUCUUUUCCUACAAAGGAGUCUUUUAGUGCUAACAUGUCCCUUCCCCACCCCUGCCAGACGGAGUCAGGAUACAAGCCUCUGGUGGGCAGAGAGGAUAGUAAGCCCCACAGUCUGAGAGGUGACUCCAUAAAACAAGAAGAGGCCCAGAAAAGCUUUGUUGACAGCUGGAGACAGAGAUCAAACACUCAAGGUUCCAUUUUGAUAAACCUGCUCCUGAAGCAGCCUUUGAUCCCAGGGUCAUCCCUAAGCCUUUGCCACCUCCUGAGUAGUAGUUCUGAGUCUCCUGCUGGCACCCCCCUGCAGCCACCAGGGUUUGGCAGUACCUUGGCUGGAAUGUCAGGCCUCAGGACCACAGGUUCUUAUGAUGGGUCAUUUUCCCUCUCAGCCCUGAGAGAAGCACAGAACCUGGCAUUCACUGGACUGAAUCUGGUUGCCCGGAAUGAGUGCUCACGUGAUGGAGACCCAGCAGAGGGAGGCAGAAGGGCCUUCCCACUCUGCCAGCUUCCUGGAGCCGUGCAUUUCCUCCCCCUUGUACAGUUCUUCAUCGGCUUACACUGCCAGGCCCUGCAGGACUUGGCAGCUGCUAAGAGAAGCGGAGCACCUGGGGACUCACCGACACAUUCCUCCUGCGUGAGCUCUGGGGUAGAGACCAACCCUGAGGACUCAGUGUGCAUCCUGGAAGGCUUCUCUGUGACUGCACUUAGCAUUCUUCAGCACCUGGUGUGCCACAGCGGAGCAGUCGUCUCCCUAUUACUGUCAGGAGUGGGGGCAGAUUCUGCUGCUGGGGAAGGAAACAGGAGCCUGGUUCACAGGCUUAGUGAUGGAGAUAUGACCUCAGCCCUAAGGGGGGUUGCUGAUGACCAAGGACAGCACCCACUGUUGAAGAUGCUUCUUCACCUGUUGGCUUUCUCUUCUGCAGCAACAGGUCACCUUCAAGCCAGUGUCCUGACCCAGUGCCUUAAGGUUUUGGUGAAAUUAGCCGAAAACACUUCCUGUGAUUUCUUGCCCAGGUUCCAGUGUGUGUUCCAAGUGCUGCCAAAGUGCCUCAGCCCAGAGACACCCCUGCCUAGCGUGCUGCUGGCUGUUGAGCUCCUCUCCCUGCUGGCGGACCACGACCAGCUGGCACCUCAGCUCUGUUCCCACUCAGAAGGCUGCCUCCUGCUGCUGCUGUACAUGUACAUCACAUCACGGCCUGACAGAGUGGCCUUGGAGACACAAUGGCUCCAGCUGGAACAAGAGGUGGUGUGGCUCCUGGCUAAGCUUGGUGUGCAGAGCCCCUUGCCCCCAGUCACUGGCUCCAACUGCCAGUGUAAUGUGGAGGUGGUCAGAGCGCUCACGGUGAUGUUGCACAGACAGUGGCUGACAGUGCGGAGGGCAGGGGGACCCCCAAGGACCGACCAGCAGAGGCGGACAGUGCGCUGUCUGCGGGACACGGUGCUGCUGCUGCACGGCCUAUCGCAGAAGGACAAGCUCUUCAUGAUGCACUGCGUGGAGGUCCUGCAUCAGUUUGACCAGGUGAUGCCGGGGGUCAGCAUGCUCAUCCGAGGGCUUCCUGAUGUGACGGACUGUGAAGAGGCAGCCCUGGAUGACCUCUGUGCCGCGGAAACCGAUGUGGAAGACCCCGAGGUGGAGUGUGGCUGAGGCCCUGAGUGUCCAGCCACAUGGUGGCACCAGCACCACUCCUUUCCUUACCACAUCAACUGAUUAAAGCAGUGACCAGCAGGAACUGCCCAGAGAACUGGCUGGCCUUGUUUCCUGAGUCUGAUCUGUUUGGCGGAGUGGGAGGGGUGGAGCAGGACCCGGACCCUGAGUGGCUGGGAUCCUUCUUCCUGUCCCUGGCUGUUGCUGAGCCCGUCCCCAUGGUAACUGAUCUGCCUUGAGGAAGGAGCCCUGCCCUGCCUGUGGAAUUGUCCUGAGUCAUUGCUUUGGGCUGGGGCCAUGGGAAGAAACCAUUGUGUGGCAGGGAAGGAGGUGGCUCUUGGCCCAGGCCUAAACCAGGAAAGCCUGGGAAACUGGGACCCACAGGUGGGCAUGAAAGGGCCGCAGCAGGGGCUCCCAGCAGUGUGUAAGACCGGGAGCUGGUCUGGCACCACUGCCCUGGUCCUUCCAGCUGCCUGUCACUGGUAUGAUGGCCCCGGUGCAUUGUGCCACCAGCAGGCCACAGCUGUGGAUCUUGGAAGGCCUCUGGGGUCCCCCGGGAGCAGGGGAGUGGGUGUGGGGGGGAACGGAUGGUGGUGAGAGGGACAGACCAGGCAGGCUGACGAGCAGGGCGGGCCUGGCUCACGUGGGCCUGUAGGCGGGCCCACGCCAAGUUUCACUUCCCGCCACUGCUGCCAGCGAGAGCCGCGGGAGAGUGUGCAGCCGAGUCACUACUGCCUGCCUGCCUGCCUGCUACGGUGAGUGUGGCCCCCACAAUGGGAUGGCGCAGGGCAGGAGGGCCAUGGGUUCCCCCACCCCAGACUAAGGGGGCACUAGGGGAGGGGCCGAGUCAUGUGAAGAGGGAGACCCUCUCAGACAGUCGAAUGUGCUGGUCCCACUAAGGAAACCACCUCACCCUCUCCAACUUCCUGCCUGAAAAUGGGCCCUGGAGCUCGCAGACAGGGCAGGAUUGUGCAGGGAAGGCCUGAGAUGUGCUUCUGCCCACCCCCUACCCCACUCCCUCCCCUUCGGAUCUUAACACUGGGCACUCACACACCCACCCCAUGCUCCUCUCCAGGCUCAGCAGCAGGUACGUACCCAACCAUGGGCUCGCAGGCCCUGCCCCCGGGGCCCAUGCAGACCCUCAUCUUUUUCGACAUGGAGGCCACUGGCUUGCCCUUCUCCCAGCCCAAGGUCACGGAGCUGUGCCUGCUGGCUGUCCACAGAUGUGCCCUGGAGAGCCCCCCCACCUCUCAGGGGCCACCUCCCACAGUUCCUCCACCACCGCGUGUGGUAGACAAGCUCUCCCUGUGUGUGGCUCCGGGGAAGGCCUGCAGCCCUGCAGCCAGCGAGAUCACAGGUCUGAGCACAGCUGUGCUGGCAGCGCAUGGGCGUCAAUGUUUUGAUGACAACCUGGCCAACCUGCUCCUAGCCUUCCUGCGGCGCCAGCCACAGCCCUGGUGCCUGGUGGCACACAAUGGUGACCGCUACGACUUCCCCCUGCUCCAAGCAGAGCUGGCUAUGCUGGGCCUCACCAGUGCUCUGGAUGGUGCCUUCUGUGUGGAUAGCAUCACUGCGCUGAAGGCCCUGGAGCGAGCAAGCAGCCCCUCAGAACACGGCCCAAGGAAGAGCUAUAGCCUAGGCAGCAUCUACACUCGCCUGUAUGGGCAGUCCCCUCCAGACUCGCACACGGCUGAGGGUGAUGUCCUGGCCCUGCUCAGCAUCUGUCAGUGGAGACCACAGGCCCUGCUGCGGUGGGUGGAUGCUCACGCCAGGCCUUUCGGCACCAUCAGGCCCAUGUAUGGGGUCACAGCCUCUGCUAGGACCAAGCCAAGACCAUCUGCUGUCACAACCACUGCACACCUGGCCACAACCAGGAACACUAGUCCCAGCCUUGGAGAGAGCAGGGGUACCAAGGAUCUUCCUCCAGUGAAGGACCCUGGAGCCCUAUCCAGGGAGGGGCUGCUGGCCCCACUGGGUCUGCUGGCCAUCCUGACCUUGGCAGUAGCCACACUGUAUGGACUAUCCCUGGCCACACCUGGGGAGUAGGCCAAGAAGGAAAAUCUGACGAAUAAAGACCCCCGCUGCCCCAUA